GUGAAGCCCGCGCAGAGCUCGCGCGUCGGUGUGGUUACAGCCGGCAGCCACGGCACCUCCUUCCGGCCGACUAGUCUCCAGGUCCCGCGGUCUGGCCCCUGGUCACCCGGCGCUGUCCCUCGUUCCUUGAAGAUCUCCAGUGCUACCUUUUGUUGAACAUCUCGAAUAGUAUCAUGUUCUAGAUAGACGGCUAGAGGGGGAAAUUCUCUGAAGGAACUAAGGAGGGGCUGGAAGGGAAGGAAGUGUUUUUAAAACUACGUGAGGCAUCAGAAUCCGAAAGCCACUUUAGUCUUAGCAAAUGUGUUUGUAGGUGUUUGAGCUUUUACUUAGAAACCUCAUUCCUUUUUCUUGCCUUCUUUUACGUUAAGCUUGAAUGUCAUGUGUUAUCUUGCUCUGAUGUUGAAACUAUAUAAGAACAUUCAUUUUUCUUUUUUUUUAAGAACAUUAAUUUUUUCUAGUCAGAGAAGGCUAAUUUUUUGAAGUUUUUUCUACACACCCAGUAAAGUCAAACAACUUUAAGUAGGAGAGCCUUACUUUAGGUAGGACUCAACGUAAAGCUUUGAAUUCCUCAAAUACUUUUUGAGUGGACUUAACAGGUUAUGUGUUUCCUGACUACGUUUCUGUUUUGCUUAUACUUCCUGAUGCUGGAAUUCUACAUGUAUUAGUUGGAUUGCACAAAGGAUGCAAAAUUUUUACAGGGAUCAGUUUUUUCUGGCGUAGCAUGUGGUUGGCUUUGUGUAUAGUUAGUUCAUUUAUUACCAGGCCCAUGGAAGUCAGACAAAAGAUUUAUGGACAAGAAGUUAUCAUUGAAAUUAAAUGGUGGCAGACAUGUCCAAGGAAUAUUGCGGGGAUUUGAUCCCUUUAUGAACCUUGUGAUAGAUGAAUGUGUGGAGAUGGCGACUAGUGGACAACAGAACAAUAUUGGAAUGGUGGUAAUACGAGGAAAUAGUAUCAUCAUGUUAGAAGCCUUGGAACGAGUAUAAAUAAUGGCUGUUCAGCAGAGAAACCCAUGUCCUCUCUCCAUAGGGCCUGUUUUACUAUGAUGUAAAAAUUAGGUCAUGUACAUUUUCAUAUUAGACUUUUUGUUAAAUAAACUUUUGUAAUAGUCAAAAAUGCUUUCUCAGAUGUUCUGAAUAUAGAAUAUCAGCUCUCAUUCCAGUUUUUUCUAACAUGAAUUUUCCUGGUUGACAUUGAUUUCAAAGGGUUUUAUGCAUUAAAGUGAAAGAAUCUUAUUAAAUGUGAAACAUGGCAAGGA